AGUGGUCCUGGCCGUGCGCCGGAGGCAGCGGCGGCGUGGCGCAGCGGCGACAUGGCCGUUGUCUCAGAGGACGACUUUCAGCACAGUUCAAACUCCACCUACAGAACCACAAGCAGCAGUCUCCGAGCUGACCAGGAGGCACUGCUUGAGAAGCUGCUGGACCGCCCGCCCCCUGGCCUGCAGAGGCCCGAGGACCGCUUCUGUGGCACAUACAUCAUCUUCUUCAGCCUGGGCAUUGGCAGUCUACUGCCAUGGAACUUCUUUAUCACUGCCAAGGAGUACUGGAUGUUCAAACUCCGCAACUCCUCCAGCCCAGCCACCGGGGAGGACCCUGAGGGCUCAGACAUCCUGAACUACUUUGAGAGCUACCUUGCCGUUGCCUCCACCGUGCCCUCCAUGCUGUGCCUGGUGGCCAACUUCCUGCUUGUCAACAGGGUUGCAGUCCACAUCCGUGUCCUGGCCUCACUGACGGUCAUCCUGGCCAUCUUCAUGGUGAUAACUGCACUGGUGAAGGUGGACACUUCCUCCUGGACCCGUGGCUUUUUUGCGGUCACCAUUGUCUGCAUGGUGAUCCUCAGCGGUGCCUCCACUGUCUUCAGCAGCAGCAUCUACGGCAUGACCGGCUCCUUUCCUAUGAGGAACUCCCAGGCACUGAUAUCAGGAGGAGCCAUGGGCGGGACGGUCAGCGCCGUGGCCUCAUUGGUGGACUUGGCUGCAUCCAGUGAUGUGAGGAACAGCGCCCUGGCCUUCUUCCUGACGGCCACUGUCUUCCUCGUGCUCUGCAUGGGACUCUACCUGCUGCUGUCCAGGCUGGAGUAUGCCAGGUGUCUAGAAGGCUCCCAAAAGCCUAUUCCUUGGAAAACAGCAUGGCACGGGAAUCAGAGAGAGAAAGGAACCAGAUCAGACGAGGAGCUCUCUCUCAAGAGUCCUGCAGAAAGAACAGAACUUACCCCCAAGAUGUGGCAACCCUUGGAGCCGUGAAUCAGCCCUUUGCUUCUCUGCAGAAGCGCACUGGCUCAUUGGUGCCCUGCAGAGGCUGAUGAAACAGAAGCAGUCAGUAAUCCAGCCGGUGGCAGCAGUUCAUGCUCCCCACCGUCUCAGCCUAGUACACAUUCCCUCUCCUUGGCCGAAGAAUUAAAGAGGACACCUUGAAAGGGUUUCUGAACUCGAUACCUACCAAAAAGAAAAAGUUCUCCCUUCCCUUUGCAGGAGCCUGAAGUCUCCCCCUUGGUUUUUUCAUUGACUUUAGUGCUGCGGAUGAUUUGGGAUGUUGGUCUAGCUGGUGACUCAUCUCAACCACAAGUGUUUUAGAAAUGAGCAGCAUGGGCCGGGCAUGGUGGUUCAUGCCUGUAAUCCCAGCACUUUGGGAGGCCGAGGCAGGCGGGCCACCUGAGGUCAGGAGUUCGAGACCAGCCUGACCAACAUGUCGAAAUCCCGUCUCUACUGAAAAUACAAAAAUUAGCCGGGCAUGGUGGUGGGCACGCCUGUAAUCCCAGCUACUCGGGAGGCUGAGUCAGGAGAAUCACUUGAACCUGGGAGGUGGAUGUUGCAGUGAGCUGAGACCAUGCCAUUGGACUCCAGCCUGGGCAAAAAGGGCAAAACUCCGUCUCAAAAAGAAAAAAAGAAAGAAAAAGAAAAAGAAAUGGGCACCAUGCCUGCCUUAAAGUAAACCAGCAGUCUCUGAGCUCAGAGAUGGGGACCAUCUUGGAGCGAUCACCUUGCAGCUAUUGGGGAAGGAGUAGUGGGGGUCUCUCAUGCUCUGUUGUAGGGGAAUGGGCUUUCAAAGAAGUGGAGGUGGCAUCUCCAUUAGAGAGAUGAUUUGCAGUUAGUGUGGAGCACAGGGGGAGUUGGGGGGCCAGCCAUGGUGAUGGCAGGGCAUAGAGAUGAUAGACUAAGUUGCAUCCACUUUGCCAGGGGAGGAGAGGCCGCUCUGUUGGGAGGGGCUGGCGGCUUGGCUGUUGGGGAUCAUCCAGGCUUUUGCUCACUCUGCUUGGUUACUCACCUUAGUGGGCACUUCACAGAGGGUCAUUCCCUCCCAGGGAGGGAGGAAGGAAAAUAAAAAUCCAUCUCCAGGCAGAAGGGUGGAUGGGGGAGUUCAGACGUGCUUGUUCCCCCUCCGCCGUGAGAAGCAGUUCGUGGGCUUUGGCUGCUCUGGAUCUCAAGUCUCAUGUGAACCCAGCAGGCUUGGAACCAGCUCAUAUGUUUGGAGGGGUGAACAAAACUCACCAAAAAGGAGGGGAGUUUUCAAUGAGGGAGGUAGAGGGGGUGCCUUGAGAGGUUGUCUUUAUCUAAGAGUUCUCUGAUUUAAUUCCAAAUGGCAGUUUUUAGGGCACCAUACACAUGUUCAUUUUCCUUCUUUUUAAUUUUUAAUGUUUUGGUUUCUUUGAGACAAGGUCUCAGUUUGUCACCCAGGCUGGAGUGCAGUGGCAUGAUCACAGCUCACUGCAGCCUCGACCUCCUGGGCUCAAGCAAUCCUCACACCUCAGCCUCCCUAGGAGCUAGGACCAUGGGUGCCUGCCACCACACGUAGCUAAUUUUUAAAAAAUUUUUUAUAGAGGCAGAGUCUCACCAUGUUGCCUAGGCUGGUCUCUAACCACUCAAGCAAACACCGUGUUUGUGUUCUAGUGUUUUGUGAAAGGUAGAACUUGAGAGUGAUGAAAUCAGAUGUUUGGCUGAGGACAUUUCUAUGCAAUGUAUUGAAAGUGUGGCUUGGCUCCUCCUGACUGCUUAUAAUAAAAUGUGAGAGAGAAAUGA